AAGAGUCUCGCACACUGUGUGAUCAUCGUUUGAGCCCAAAGUGCUAAAAUACAGGUGUAGGUGUUUGAGAAGCGCUGUAGUUGAUUAUGGACGAAAUGCCUAAUUUAAGGAGCAGAGGCGGAGUGGAAAAUGAAAAAAGCUUCACCGCAGUGGAGACUUGUUAACAGCCCUGGGGAGAAAGGGGCUUAACAGAGUCUGGAAAUCGUGAAAGAGCUUGACCGAUGAAAUGGGCCUGGCUGUCGUAUCGGUAAUUUGGUGAAUGUUGCUUAAGAUCAGCCUGGAAAGGUAGUUAGUCAGAUCCGAAGUGACAUAUUUGCACUGCCAAAGGAGGCUCUGGAGGUUAAAGUAUGUGUUUUAAUUUCGUUGUUGAGGCCAUAUAAUGCAGAGUUGACGGACCGACCUUAUGAGUCACCUUGGAGCGGAGUAGUGGAGACUUAAAGACAGACUACCCUGGAGCUGGCUUCAAACUAGUUCUUAAUAUUGUGACUCGAACUCCCCAUCCCCAGAAAUUCUCAGAUCUUAGAAGCCAAAGACUGGCAAGGAUACUAGAGGGAACUACUCGAGUAGGCGAGGUCAGACUACAUACCGAAUAGGAGUCCUUCCAAAAAUAUGCAGUUUCACAUACAGCUGGGUACUCCAAGUGUACAGUUCCCAUCAGCUCUAAUAUGACAGAAGGCUGAGGCCGGGGUGCUAGAGAACCUUGCCGUGCUGGAAUUCACGUUGACGCCCCCACGGAGCUCUGCUGCAGAGCCCUCGAGUCCCGCACUUCCGGCCGCCAGGUGGCGCUGGUUCUGUUGCCAACUCGGAGAGACUGAGCUGGGCCACGCAAGAUGGCGCCGUCCGCCUUGCUGCGUCCCCUUUCCCGGCUGCUGGCCCCCGCCAGGCUCCCGAGCGGCCCUUCAGUGCGAUCAAAGUUCUACGUGCGAGAGCCGCCGAAUGCCAAACCUGACUGGCUGAAAGUUGGGUUCACCUUGGGCACCACUGUCUUCUUGUGGAUCUAUCUCAUCAAACAACACAAUGAAGAUAUUUUAGAGUACAAAAGAAGAAAUGGGCUGGAAUAAACUUUUGAAACACUAAUGUAGUAUGCUCCGUAUAGUGAUUGUAGCUGUUCCUCUGGAUUCACCAUCUGUUGAGUUGUAAAUGUGAGAGAAAAAGUUAUAUGUGAAUAUAUAUCAAGCCAGCAUUUGUAUUUUGCAUCAUUAAAUAAAAAGAAAUAAAAAUACUUCUGUAUUCUUCAGAUAAAGCAUAUUGUGACAA